GAAGUCAGUAAACCACAGCCUUCAGCAUGCUCUGCUCAGGCGGCAGCAGUGGCUUUUUGGAGGUGUCUCGGCCAUGACACACAUUUGACAUGCCCUCCCUCAACCUACUUAUAGACUAUUUUUCUUGCUCUGCAGCAUGGACCAAAGAGAAAUUCUGCAGAAGUUCCUGGAUGAGGCCCAAAGCAAGAAAAUUACUAAAGAGGAGUUUGCCAAUGAAUUUCUGAAGCUGAAAAGGCAAUCUACCAAGUACAAGGCAGACAAAACCUAUCCUACAACUGUGGCUGAGAAGCCCAAGAAUAUCAAGAAAAACAGAUAUAAGGAUAUUUUGCCCUAUGAUUAUAGCCGGGUAGAACUAUCCCUGAUAACCUCUGAUGAGGAUUCCAGCUACAUCAAUGCCAACUUCAUUAAGGGAGUUUAUGGACCCAAGGCUUAUAUUGCCACCCAGGGUCCUUUAUCUACAACCCUCCUGGACUUCUGGAGGAUGAUUUGGGAAUAUAGUGUCCUUAUCAUUGUUAUGGCAUGCAUGGAGUAUGAAAUGGGAAAGAAAAAGUGUGAGCGCUACUGGGCUGAGCCAGGAGAGAUGCAGCUGGAAUUUGGCCCUUUCUCUGUAUCCUGUGAAGCUGAAAAAAGGAAAUCUGAUUAUAUAAUCAGGACUCUAAAAGUUAAGUUCAAUAGUGAAACUCGAACUAUCUACCAGUUUCAUUACAAGAAUUGGCCAGACCAUGAUGUACCUUCAUCUAUAGACCCUAUUCUUGAGCUCAUCUGGGAUGUACGUUGUUACCAAGAGGAUGACAGUGUUCCCAUAUGCAUUCACUGCAGUGCUGGCUGUGGAAGGACUGGUGUUAUUUGUGCUAUUGAUUAUACAUGGAUGUUGCUAAAAGAUGGGAUAAUUCCUGAGAACUUCAGUGUUUUCAGUUUGAUCCGGGAAAUGCGGACACAGAGGCCUUCAUUAGUUCAAACGCAGGAACAAUAUGAACUGGUCUACAAUGCUGUAUUAGAACUAUUUAAGAGACAGAUGGAUGUUAUCAGAGAUAAACAUUCUGGAACAGAGAGUCAAGCAAAGCAUUGUAUUCCUGAGAAAAAUCACACUCUCCAAGCAGACUCUUAUUCUCCUAAUUUACCAAAAAGUACCACAAAAGCAGCAAAAAUGAUGAACCAACAAAGGACAAAAAUGGAAAUCAAAGAAUCUUCUUCCUUUGACUUUAGGACUUCUGAAAUAAGUGCAAAAGAAGAGCUAGUUUUGCACCCUGCUAAAUCAAGCACUUCUUUUGACUUUCUGGAGCUAAAUUACAGUUUUGACAAAAAUGCUGACACAACCAUGAAAUGGCAGACAAAGGCAUUUCCAAUAGUUGGGGAGCCUCUUCAGAAGCAUCAAAGUUUGGAUUUGGGCUCUCUUUUGUUUGAGGGAUGUUCUAAUUCUAAACCUGUAAAUGCAGCAGGAAGAUAUUUUAAUUCAAAGGUGCCAAUAACACGGACCAAAUCAACUCCUUUUGAAUUGAUACAGCAGAGAGAAACCAAGGAGGUGGACAGCAAGGAAAACUUUUCUUAUUUGGAAUCUCAACCACAUGAUUCUUGUUUUGUAGAGAUGCAGGCUCAAAAAGUAAUGCAUGUUUCUUCAGCAGAACUGAAUUAUUCACUGCCAUAUGACUCUAAACACCAAAUACGUAAUGCCUCUAAUGUAAAGCACCAUGACUCUAGUGCUCUUGGUGUAUAUUCUUACAUACCUUUAGUGGAAAAUCCUUAUUUUUCAUCAUGGCCUCCAAGUGGUACCAGUUCUAAGAUGUCUCUUGAUUUACCUGAGAAGCAAGAUGGAACUGUUUUUCCUUCUUCUCUGUUGCCAACAUCCUCUACAUCCCUCUUCUCUUAUUACAAUUCACAUGAUUCUUUAUCACUGAAUUCUCCAACCAAUAUUUCCUCACUAUUGAACCAGGAGUCAGCUGUACUAGCAACUGCUCCAAGGAUAGAUGAUGAAAUCCCCCCUCCACUUCCUGUAUGGACACCUGAAUCAUUUAUUGUGGUUGAGGAAGCUGGAGAAUUCUCACCAAAUGUUCCCAAAUCCUUAUCCUCAGCUGUGAAGGUAAAAAUUGGAACAUCACUGGAAUGGGGUGGAACAUCUGAACCAAAGAAAUUUGAUGACUCUGUGAUACUUAGACCAAGCAAGAGUGUAAAACUCCGAAGUCCUAAAUCAGACAGAGAGAAAAAAGGAGGGAAUUCCAGCAGCAGGGAUCAGCCUACCAAUGACUCAAAGGUAGAAAUGAGCAUGAUGUGUAUGGAGAAAUGGUGAGUAGGCUAUUUUUUUUUUGCAAUAGAUAUUCUAGUUUGUGAAAUACAGAAAAUAAAUUUGGGUAAAUAAGAUGUGGGGCAAGAUUCUGAAGGACUUAAAAAAGCUAGUCACAUGAAAUAUCCAGAAUAGACAGAUCCAUAAAGAUAGAAGCAGAUUAGUGAUUGCCAGGGGCUGGGGGAAAGAGGAAAAUAAGGAGUGAUGACUUAAUGGGUGCAGAGUUUCCUUCUAGGGUGAUAAAAAGUAUUCUGGAACUAAAUUGUGGUGAUGGUUGUACAAUACUGUGAAUGUGCUAAAUGUCACUAAUGGCAAAUCUUAUGUGUAUUUUACUACCCAAAGUUAGGCAGAGGAAUUUACACCCAAAGUUAGGCAGAGGAAUUUAGAUUUAAUGUAGUAAGUAACAGGCAUUAUGGGUUCUUUGUUAGGGGAGUAUUAAGAUGAAAUGGAAUUUUAGGGAAAUAAUUACUAGAAUACUGUUAACGAACAACUUUAGUUUUCAGAAUAUUCCCUAACAGCAAACUGGAAGAUGAUGAACUACUUCAGAGUAGUUAUUAAGUAUUUAUUAAAUGCCUACUGUAUGCCAGUUAUUUUAUUAGGUGCUAGAAAUAAGUACUACACUUGUGUGUAUUACCUAGCAUGUAAGAAAUAAGACAAUUUAUUGAUAAGACAAAUUCUAAGGACUAAACAAACCCAAUGACCAAUGACAUGUGAACCUCUUGUACUUUACUGCAUUUUCAUUUUCAAAAGGAAUUAAUAUAAUAGUAAUACUCAGCACCAUAUAAUUAAAUGCUUAUGUCAGUAGAAUACCAUCUGUAUCUUCAGAAAUUUACAUCAUGGGAAAAUAUGUCCAUUACUGAAAAUCUUCAUCAUGGAAAAUUUCAAACACACAUUUAAAACCUACCUUAUCACACCAAUAAAAUUAAUAAUAAUUCCUUAAUAGUAACUAAUAUCCAGACUGUUCAGUUUUCAAUUGUCUCAAAAAUGUCUUUUUACAGUUGGUUUAUUCAAAUCUGGAUUCAAACAAAAUCUAAGCAUUUCAUUUGAUUUGUAUGUUUGUCUUCUUAAAUCUGUCUUUUGAAAUCUGUAACAGUUCUCCCUUCUUUUUUUAAUAUUUUCUUUUUAAAUAUAUAACCGUUCUCCUUUCUAUACUUUUCACAUCAUUUAUUUGUUGAAGAGAGUGGGUCAUUUGUCUUAAAAGACUGCUUAGUCUUCUAGAUUUGGCUAAUUGUAUCACAAUGGUUUUAUUUAACAUCCUCUAUGCCCAAUAUUUCAUGCAAAAUGGGUGUUAGAUCUAGAAGCUUGAUUAUAUUCGGUUUCAGUGUCUUUGGGAGAAUACUUCUGAAGUGAGCUAUACAUUUUUGAUGAAUCAUAGGCUCAUAGGCUAACGAGGUAGAAAAACAAAGUUCUUGAGGCUCCAGUCAUUUUUCAGAUAAUAUUUUAUUUGGUGAUUGUCGGCUAAGAUUGAUUGAUUAAAAAAUUAUACAAAGAGAAAAGGGUGUUGACUUAUGACUUUUAAUUGAUGGAUUUCUCUGGU